ACGCUCGCCUUGAACCGGGACUCGAGAGGCAGAAGCAAGGCACGGGUCCCCUUUCUCCUCUCCUCCACCAAACCACCGCAGCCCAGCACGUGAAGCUUCCCUUUGUUCAUCCGAGGCUCGCUUUUCUCCCCAGCAGAUCCACCUGGAUGCUCUCCCUCGAGCAGCGCGGGGAGCCCGGGGAGAUGCAGGACCACCCACUGGCGGGGAAGCAGCUAGCAGCCCUCCCGCGCCCCCGCGCUGCCGAGCGCCUUCUGCCUCCGCGCUCGGACGAGAGCCCGUGCCGGCCCCGGCCCCGGCCCCACCGCGCCAACGCCGCCCGCCCGGCCGCCCCGCAGCCCCGCCGCCCCGCAGCCCCGCACCGCGCUGGCCAGGCUCCCGCGACAGUGGCCCCGCAGUAAGUUGGCAGGAGCGAGUCCCCUCCGUUCUCGCCUCCCCCGCACCUUUUGAACUUGUUGCUGCUGCUCUGCUCGCCUGCGCCUGGCUUUUGGAAGGUGAAAAGGAGGAGGGAGGCACGGAGGGAUGGGGGAAGGGAAAGAAGAGCUCGCUUGAGCUUUAUUUAUGCUCUCUCGGCGCAUCGGAUUCGGCUGCUCGCGAGCUGCUUUCUCUCCUCUUCCCUUUCCGGGUGCACGGCGAGGAGAAAGUCUCUAUGCAACUAAGCCCCGGCGCGCACUUGGCCAGGUAUGUACCGCGGGAGCGGCGCGUUCUGCGCGGAAGCAGAUGCUGCUGCCGCCACGGCGGCGGCGGCUGCCAGCUCCUGAGCUCUGUAACUGUCACACUGCACCUGAGCUGAACUUGAAAAGAGAGUGAAGGGGCGAUUGGGCGAACGCUUUUGGCAGACACAGAGGGUGUUUGUAGACGUGGGGGAGGAGAAUCUCUAUUAACGCCCCCCACCGUAACCACUGCACAUCACCUCCAUCUCUGCAAAUACAGCCCGAGGAGUAGAGGCAGCAGCAGCUGGACCCCCAAAGAGAGACGUGGGGCAGCGGCUGUGACCGCAUCUCCUGAGCUACAACAACAGGUCGCCUUUUUGAGACUCCUUUGGCGGGAAGGGCUACUUGGAAAGGAAGGUUUGAAAGAGUGAGAAGGGUAGGUGUAAGGGUUCCCUAAUUCGUCGAAAGAAUUCUAUUGGGUGACUCUCGUUCGUCUUCUCUAUCCUACACUCCACAUACUGACCCUAUAUUAUCCAGACUGUGCCGGGGAGAAAUCAAAAACACCUGUUUGAAGAAACGGCUGCACCUGUGUGCUUAUUUGUGCCAGAGGGUGGCCUAGCCCACCUGCAGGAAGAGAUUUGGCUGGGUUCUGUUGAGGGUGAUUGUUAGGACGUUGUAUUUUGUUGCCAUUAUUCCAAAUACCUGUCUUGGAGGGAAAGUUGCCCUUCUGAGAACUGUGACUUUACCAGGAGCCCUAUCUUGGAAUAAGAGUUACACCUCUGGACCACGUUUCUCACUAGUACUUUGCUUGACUGGAGGAAGUGGGUGACUUUUGGCUGCUUCGGUGACCCAUUGUAGACGCCUCGUUACCCUUCUUCCUUCCGCUUCAAGUAAUCAUGGCGGCGGGGGUGGCAGCGUGGCUGCCUUUUGCAAGGGCAGCGGCUAUCGGGUGGAUGCCUGUGGCCUCGGGGCCUAUGCCGGCUCCCCCGAGGCAGGAGAGGAAAAGGACCCAAGAUGCUCUCAUUGUGCUGAAUGUGAGUGGCACCCGCUUCCAGACGUGGCAGGACACCCUGGAACGUUACCCAGACACUCUACUGGGCAGUUCUGAGAGGGACUUUUUCUACCACCCAGAAACUCAGCAGUAUUUCUUUGACCGUGACCCAGACAUCUUCCGCCACAUCCUGAAUUUCUACCGCACUGGGAAGCUCCACUAUCCUCGCCACGAGUGCAUCUCUGCUUACGAUGAAGAACUGGCCUUCUUUGGCCUCAUCCCGGAAAUCAUCGGCGACUGCUGUUAUGAGGAGUACAAGGAUCGCAGGCGAGAGAACGCCGAGCGCCUGCAGGACGACGCGGAUACCGACACCGCUGGGGAGAGCGCCUUGCCCACCAUGACUGCAAGGCAGAGGGUCUGGAGGGCCUUCGAGAACCCCCACACCAGCACGAUGGCCCUGGUGUUCUACUAUGUCACGGGGUUUUUCAUUGCCGUCUCUGUCAUCGCGAAUGUGGUGGAAACAGUGCCGUGCGGAUCAAGCCCAGGUCACAUUAAAGAACUGCCCUGUGGAGAGCGGUAUGCUGUGGCCUUCUUCUGCUUGGACACGGCCUGCGUCAUGAUCUUCACAGUUGAGUAUUUGCUUCGCCUGGCUGCAGCGCCUAGUCGUUACCGUUUUGUGCGUAGUGUCAUGAGUAUCAUCGACGUGGUGGCCAUCCUGCCUUAUUACAUUGGGCUGGUGAUGACAGACAAUGAGGACGUCAGCGGAGCCUUUGUCACACUCCGAGUCUUCCGGGUCUUCAGGAUCUUUAAGUUUUCCCGCCACUCUCAAGGCCUGCGCAUCCUGGGGUACACACUGAAGAGUUGUGCCUCAGAAUUGGGCUUCUUGCUUUUCUCGCUCACCAUGGCUAUCAUCAUCUUCGCUACAGUUAUGUUCUACGCAGAGAAGGGGUCUUCGGCUAGCAAGUUCACCAGCAUCCCUGCAGCCUUCUGGUAUACCAUCGUCACCAUGACAACACUAGGGUAUGGUGACAUGGUGCCAAAAACCAUAGCAGGGAAGAUUUUUGGUUCUAUCUGUUCGCUGAGUGGGGUCUUGGUCAUUGCUCUACCUGUUCCGGUGAUUGUAUCCAACUUCAGUCGCAUCUACCACCAGAAUCAACGAGCAGACAAACGAAGGGCACAAAAGAAAGCUAGACUGGCCAGGAUCCGGGCAGCCAAAAGCGGAAGCGCAAAUGCUUACAUGCAGAGCAAACGGAAUGGUUUACUCAGUAAUCAGCUGCAGUCCUCAGAGGAUGAGCAGGCUUUUGUUAGCAAAUCCGGCUCCAGCUUUGAAACCCAGCACCACCACCUGCUUCACUGCCUGGAAAAAACCACGAAUCACGAGUUUGUGGACGAACAAGUCUUUGAAGAAAGCUGCAUGGAAGUUGCAACUGUUAAUCGUCCUUCAAGUCACAGUCCUUCACUGUCUUCACAACAAGGAGUCACCAGCACCUGCUGUUCACGACGACACAAAAAAACUUUUCGCAUCCCAAAUGCCAAUGUAUCAGGAAGCCAUCAAGGUAGUAUACAAGAACUCAGCACGAUUCAGAUCAGAUGUGUGGAGAGAACACCUCUGUCUAACAGCCGAUCCAGUUUAAAUGCCAAAAUGGAAGAGUGUGUUAAACUAAACUGUGAACAACCUUAUGUGACUACAGCAAUAAUAAGCAUCCCAACACCUCCAGUAACCACACCAGAAGGAGACGAUAGGCCAGAAUCCCCUGAGUACUCAGGAGGAAAUAUUGUCAGAGUUUCUGCUUUGUAAGACAAUUGGAAUAAGGUCUAAGAGAAUUCGAGCCCUGGCUGUGAAAAGAAUCUCAACAUAGAAGAAAGAAGAAACAAUAAAUAUUCUGCAGAUUAAUGCAGCAAAGAAAGAAGGUUGGUAGUGAAACACAAAGCUUCCAAUCUUAAGGAUGUGAAUAAAACCACCAAAUGGCAUUUCUAGACAGUUUGACCUGUUAUACAGAGUAAUAUUCUGUGGCCCUUUGACUUUGUGAAUGAGCACAAUGAAAUGCCGCCUACUGAUGCUUCUUAUGAUCAGAACUCUUUUUUAAUAAAAUAAAUAACAUAAAUCGUUGAACAUAAUGUUCCAGUUGAAUGCAAAACAAAAAAAAUAUGGAAAACAUUUUGAUAAAAUUUUUUCCUGUUAAAACCAUGAACAUUGGCUAUGAUGAAGAUUAUUACAUAUGAAAAAAAAACUCACACAACAUAUUUGUAUUGACUGAAGGAAACCAUCAUAAUGCAUGCUAGAAUUCUUUGAAGCAGUGAUCUCAGUUUCCUUAUGUUGUCUUCAGAAUAGGCAUGAUAAACUAUAAUUGUAGAAAGGGGUAAUUUCUGUGCACUUACAACAAGCUGAGUGUUCAUGUUCCAUGGUGGGCUGUGCAAAUAAACUCCUUUUAGACCUGCAGUAUUUCUCAUGGGGAUGCUCAUUAGUAAAUCUAAAGUGUUCAGAUAGUUCAGUAUUCAUUAUCGUUUAACUUUGCACCUAGAUACUGUUACAACUGCAAUAAUUUGUUGUACAACUGUUGUAUCAGGAAUCAGGAUUUUUUUGUUGUUGUACUUUCCAGAUCCUUAUAGAUACGGUAAGAGCCACAUUCGUAGAAAAACUUCUGGUGUGGCCAGGUUUUAGGUAACUUUUUAAUCCAAAACUAUUGUGCCAUAAAUGUUUUUCAGUAAUAUUUUUUGGUCCACUGUAUUCCUGUGACACAGUGCAUUAUCUGUUCUUGUAUUUCUAUAGCACCUCUCUAUUGGGUUUAUCAUCAUCAACAAGACUACUGUUUACUGUAGUUCAAGUGACUUUCCUACUUUUGUAUUUCCAAAAAAAAUUAUCUUGUAAGUAGCUUGUCAUCAAUCCCCUUGUCGAAAACUAGAAAAAAAGGAGUUGACCCAUAUAAAUUAUCUCUAACGUCUUUGUUGUUUAUGGAAAAGCCCAGAUACUGGAUAUAUCACUAUGUAUUUUAUGAACAGAAUUGACUGGGACUAAUAUCACAGGAUCAAUCAUCUCAGAAUCUUACUUGAUGCAUUAUUUAUUUUGCUUUAGAUCUUGAAUACAUUUUGAGAAUAACUAAUGUGGAUUGAAAUGUAGAGAUACACUGGAGUGCUUUAUUUAGCAAUAUUUGAUGAAAGCAUGCUUUCUACGCCAUUCAGGAAGGCAGCACAAAUUUAUCUCAGAAAGGUUCCUGUGUAUUGCAAGGUACAAUUUUCUCCAAUAAAUCAGGAGAACAGGAGUUUGAUGAUGCAAAGUUGAUCUCUGUACAUUUAAGUGAAAAGUCUUUAUAACUUUUCACCCUUAAAAUAUUUCAGCAGACAUGUCUGCACAUGACAGUGUAAAAAAGUUUAAUGUCAAAUGCAAAGUUUUUAUUCAUUCCAAGCCACCACUGUAAGGAAUAAAGCUUAGCUUCUGUACAUGGAAAGAGCUAAUAAUUAUCCCUCUGUCAGAGAUGAGAUUUUUAAAUGCUUAUGAUAUUUAAUCAUAAAAAGGGAUUAAUCCAACCAUUUUCUAGUAAAGCCAGAAAUUCUUGCUUCCCAUUUCUAGAAUAGUUUCUAGAACAGUGCUAUGCACAUAUUAGAUCUUAAUAAACAUUUGCUGAGUGAAAGUAAGAUAAACUCAACUAUCUCUUGGGAAGAACUGGCUUCAUUCCUAGUACAUCUUUUAAAAAGUUACUAAUUUUCCAGCAGUACAAAUAUUAACAAUUAUAUUAACACCUGCCUCAUGUCAGUUUAUGCUUCUAGAGCAAUGUCUAGUGAAACUUAUCUGAUGGCAUUUAUUGAAAACCUUCUAAAAAGUAGACUAAGGAAACCAUAAUCAGAAUUACUAUGUCUUUUGAUUCCCAAUGAGAAGUUCUAUUUUCAUGUUCUUAAUAUUACAUACAAGAAAAUGCAGUUAGGUUAUUUCAAUUGACAAUUCUGCCUCCUCUUUUGAUUUAUCACUUACCCAAAAUUAUUAAUUUUAUUAGGCUUUUGGAAAAGAAAAAAAACUUUUUGAUGUUUUAGGUGAUUUAAAAAUAUACCGUGUUGGUGGUGAAUGACUAUUGAUGACUGUGUUAAGUGCAUCUGUAUUGUAAGUGAAAUGUAAUUAUUUCUGUGUACCAUAUGGAGUAACUAAGGUCAUUGUUUUUGACAAUUUUGUUUGAAAUUCAUAUAUCUUAUUUCAAAGGAUAGCAUAAUAUCUGCAUUAUGCUGGAAAAAAAUAGACCUUUGGAGAAUACUUAAAUAAAACAUGUGCAUGCUUGAACAGGACAAAA